AUUUACCUGUUUCUUAGAGCUUUGACUCAGCUCAAAACUUAACCAAGACAUUAGUCAAAGGUUAGCAAAAUCACUCUGAUGGUUACUCUCAUGGUGCCGGUUUGUUUGUUUAUCCCACAUGCAGGGGAAGUGACACUGAGAAGCAUCGGGUCUCUUGGUCCACAGCCUCCACAUUUCUUUUCAGCAGGAUGAGGAGGGAGAUGUGUGUCUACUCGUGGGGUGGGGGUAGUGAGGCCUGUGUCAUGGUCAUUCCCCUUCUCCCACCUCAUGUUUUAGGGAGGAAAAGUUCAGAUGGGGGAGAGAGUGAGUGUGCCUGUGUGUGUGGGAGACAGCUACUGUUGAUACACUGUGUGAAUUACUUUCAACUCUUUUGUAGUAAGCACCCAGGCUGGUCAGUGGCUCCUUUUAAAUCUUCUAUUAAAAUAUUUACUUUAAAUUAGAGAAUUAAAAAUGUACUUAUUUUUAAUGAAUUAAGAAAAUAAGUCAUUAUUUUACUUUUUGCAAUUACUUAGUCCGAUUCAAAUGACAUUUGGCCACAGAUAUGAGAGAUGGCAAACUAUAUCUAAGAUGGGAUAUAAAAUGAAAAGUAUAUACUUUUUAAAGAUGUUUCUUUUUAAAGAUGUUUCUUUGAAGAAUAUUGGCUUUCCCGGUAAAUUUAGAAGAAAAACAUUACAGAAAUUGUGAGAAUAAUGUGGAAUUAGAUGUGAAACUAGUUUAAGAAAAUAUUUUUCACCAAAAAAAUCAGAUCUGGUGUGUGACAUUAAUAGCUUUCUUUUUUUUUGAGCUGUACUUAGUGUAUUUUGUAAUUAUUUACAAACUUUGCUCCAGUUGUAUCUUAGGAUAAAUUGUCUUAUUCUUUUGUAUAGUUAACCUUUAUAGUUGCACAAAAGAUAAAAGAUAAAAAUUACCUUUAUGGACAUUGGAAGAAAGAUGUUAUCAAAUACAUUGUGUGGCUUUGACAUACAUUCUUAGCAGAAUGUACAGACACUUCUGCUUUAUGUGAACUGGCAUUUCUGAAUAUGCAUUAAAUAGAAGUAAUUAUUGAAAUGGGAGACAGAAAGGUUAAUUUUAAUGUUGUUAUGAAUGACAUUUUUUUGGGGAUCUUGAGAAACGAUUGUCUUUACUGAUGAUUUAUUAUAGUCAUCCACCCCCUUCUGCCAUUCAUCAGCUUAAACAUUAGUGUGUUAUGUAAUUAUUGACAUUUUCAUCAUUAGAUUUAGCAAGCAUUUACAAUAUAUUAACAAAAUCUUCAGUACAUGAAAGGCAUUUAUUACUUCCUUGAAAAUAAAGGACUGGAAUUAGUGGAAUCAAGGAAUAGUUUAAUUCAACCAGGACCACCUUUACUCUGUGGCAAGGAUGGAACAGUGGGUAGAAUAUGAAGAUGAAUGAGACUCAGUACUGCCUUCAAGGGAGAAGCAGACAUACACAGAGCUCUCUAUCAAUAUCAGCUCACAUCAUUGAAAAGAUAAUUUUGAAGACAUGUUUUGCUGAAAAGACACUAAGAAAAAUUUUACGAAUGGGAUGAACAUGCUCCAGUUAAUUGACUACCUACUGCAAUUUGAAUGUUAACAUUACCCAUCUGGUACAGUUACCUAGUGAUGUACCUAUUUUCACAAUACCCUGUUUCAGUGUGCUUGUCUUGAUUAAAGAAUUCAAAGUGGAGUACCGCAAACUUGAUAUGGAAAAUAAAAAGAAAGACAAGGACAAAUCAGAUGAUAGAAUGGCACGACCUAGUGGUCGAUCGGGACACAACACUCGAGGAACUGGGUCUUCAUCGUCUGGAGUUUUAAUGGUUGGACCUAACUUUAGAGUUGGAAAAAAAAUUGGAUGUGGCAAUUUUGGAGAAUUACGAUUAGACCAGAGGGAGAAACCCGAAGGCUGUCAGGGUACCUCUGCAUCCUUAAUAUGUGACUUCCGUCUCUGUGCACAAGGGAAAAAUUUAUACACAAAUGAAUAUGUGGCAAUUAAGUUGGAGCCCAUGAAAUCAAGAGCACCACAGCUACAUUUGGAAUACAGAUUCUAUAAGCAGUUAGGAUCUGGAGAUGGUAUACCUCAAGUUUACUAUUUCGGCCCUUGUGGUAAAUACAAUGCUAUGGUGCUGGAACUGCUGGGACCUAGUUUGGAAGACUUGUUUGACUUGUGUGACAGAACAUUUUCUCUUAAAACAGUUCUCAUGAUAGCUAUACAACUGAUUUCUCGCAUGGAAUAUGUCCAUUCAAAGAACUUGAUAUACAGAGAUGUAAAACCUGAGAACUUCUUAAUAGGACGACCAGGAAACAAAACCCAGCAAGUUAUUCACAUUAUAGAUUUUGGUUUGGCAAAGGAAUAUAUUGAUCCGGAGACAAAGAAACACAUACCAUACAGAGAACACAAGAGCCUUACAGGAACAGCUAGAUAUAUGAGCAUAAACACACAUUUAGGAAAAGAACAAAGUAGAAGAGACGAUUUAGAAGCUUUAGGUCAUAUGUUCAUGUAUUUUCUGAGAGGCAGUCUUCCUUGGCAAGGCUUAAAGGCUGACACAUUAAAGGAGAGGUAUCAGAAAAUUGGAGAUACAAAACGGGCUACACCAAUAGAAGUGUUAUGUGAAAAUUUUCCAGAAGAAAUGGCAACAUAUCUUCGUUAUGUAAGAAGGCUAGAUUUUUUUGAAAAACCAGACUAUGACUACUUAAGAAAGCUUUUUACUGACUUGUUUGAUCGAAAAGGAUAUAUGUUUGAUUAUGAAUAUGACUGGAUUGGUAAACAGUUGCCUACUCCAGUGGGUGCAGUUCAGCAAGAUCCUGCUCUGUCAUCAAACAGAGAAGCACAUCAACACAGAGAUAAGAUGCAACAAUCCAAAAACCAGUCGGCAGACCACAGGGCAGCUUGGGACUCCCAGCAGGCAAAUCCCCACCAUUUGAGAGCUCACCUUGCAGCAGACAGACAUGGUGGCUCGGUACAGGUUGUAAGUUCUACAAAUGGAGAGUUAAACACAGAUGACCCCACCGCAGGACGUUCAAAUGCACCCAUCACAGCCCCUACUGAAGUAGAAGUGAUGGAUGAAACCAACUGCCAGAAAGUGUUGAACAUGUGGUGCUGCUGUUUUUUCAAACGAAGGAAAAGGAAAACCAUACAGCGCCACAAAUGACUCUGGACACAGACAGAUCCUGGGGAGUUACUUACAUGUUCAUCUGCUGUCUUGUGAUUAAAAUCAUCUCUGUAGUGACCACGUAUAUUUUCAAGGACUCACUCUUAGAAACAAAAAUGUCAUACUUUCAUACUUCAUUUUGUGGUUGUCUUACAUUCUUUUUCUUUUUUUUUUUUUCUCUAAUUUAACCUUUAUGGAAGCUUUAAAGUUUUGUCAAAACAUGAGUGCUUUGCCCAUCAGUGAAUGGAAUGGACCAAUGAGGUGGUAUCAAUGAAUAUAGUUCCAUAGAACAUUUUCCAGAAGUUCUUCUGUUGUAGAAAGCAGUACAGUAUCUUAAGUGUCAACCAGUUAUAUACCUAAUCUGGUUUUUUAUAACUUCUGUAAGAGCAUAAUCAAACAGGAAUUUUCUUUUCUCAGUGGAUAAUACAACAGAGAAAACAGAGUUGCCCAAAUAUUUAAAAGAAGUUAUUCCUUGAGAAGUUCAUAUUUUGUGACAUCUGCAUUGAUUUCAGUAUUACUGAUGGUACUGUUAUUCAUAAGUCAUAUUAACAUUCUCUCCGUGAAAUCAUGGUACAGUCACUGCCCAGAGGUACUGAGGAAAAAGCAAUAUGGGUUCGGCAGAUGGUGGUGGUAAAAUGAAUCUUAAGGAGUGUGGUAAAUAUGUGCUCCGCUUUUGUUGCAUCACUAUGUGAAGUACUGUGUUGCAGAAGUGGCAAAAGCGCUUAUUUUUAAAAAUGCAAAAUAUUUGUACAAUGUAACUUUAUGCUUCCAAAUAAUAAUGUAUGUUAGACAGCAAGAAAUGAAUACUUUAAAAAGUGAUGUAUGUUGGAGUUAUAAAGAAAUACACUAAGGAGAGGUAGUAAAUGUGAACCUUGUUGCAGUGUAUAAGGUGGAAGCCUAAAGAAAUCUCACCGAAACUUACUGCUGAAUGAUUACAUUCUCCCUUAAGCAGAAAACUUUGGAUGUGCCAUGCAAUGGUGUCUGUGUAAUUAUUUUGCUCUUUGAUUAAAAAAAAGACCCCCAGCAAUAAAAAGUGGGUCACUCUAUGCCCUCUGUGCACAUUAGUCUCUUGUAUUCAACUUUGCUGAUUCUCUGGAAUUUUCCUACUCUUUAGCAUAAUUUUGAUGAUUGAAAAAUAUUUUGGAAAGGAUGGGUCAGGUGCUUUGCCUCCAUAGUCUUUUGAAGUGCCUGCAUAUGAACAACAACAACAACAACAAAAAAUUCUGUAAAAAAGGAAGCCCAUUCCACUUUUCAAGUAUGCUUUGUUUUAAGCCAUAAAGACACACAUGUAGUUUUGUCACAUUCUACUAGCCAAAAUUUUCAAGAAGGGUUAAAACAAAGACUGGCUAGAAAGAUAAUUAUUUUGAAUAAAUCUCAUAUUCAUCUUUCAUUUAUAUAAUUGUUACUUAUUCCUCCCAUGCAGUCUCUUCGUUGUCUUUAAGUGUGUGCCUCCAGGCAUGCUUAUUUAUUUUUAUUGUCUCAAGGUAACAUUUAAGAUGUAUAUUAAAGUAAAGCUACAUUUUUUUACUUCAUUAUUGCAUUUACAGGGAUUUAAUUGUACUUUGUAAUUUAUUUUUCUUAUUAGCCAAAAGUUUAAUGCAUUUUUUUUUGAUGAAUUAGGCACCCACAUGAACACCACAAAUCAGGACAUUGUUUAUCAUUGUUGCUAUGAAUCCUAUGAAUGAUCUUUUUUUUAUUUUAAAGACCUACACUUAACCUACAAAACAUUUGCUGUAUAAUUUGGUCAACAGUUUCUAUCUAUCUGUAUACUGUCAUGAUGUCUUAAACUGCAGGAGUUACAUACUGAGUUUAUAUUUUUAUUUGCUUUGAGCAAGGUAGAUAAACAUUUUGGCCAUUAUAAUGUGAAACCACUUCUUCUUUCUUUACAGUAUUUGACCAAACUUGUGUGUCUAUGAUAUUUGUAAAUACAUGCGAAUAUCUGUAUUUCUUAUCAUAAGCCUAUUUAGUUUUAUUCUCAGUAGGGUUUUUUGGAUUGUACAGUGUUUAUAUGAUCUGAACUCCUUAUACAUAAGAAGGUGUGUAUAUUAAUCCAAUUAUGGACUUAAAAUAUUUUAAAAGUAUAAAUACCCUUAUUUGCUGCAAAGACCAGUGUGUAGGCAUUUGCUUUUUAGCAAUAUUUUUAAGUGCUCCAUUUUAAUGCCGAGGAAUAAGUCUUUUGGCAACACAAACUGGUCAAUAAUAGGUAAUGCAGGUAUGUUCAGGUUAAGCCAACAAUGUUUUGCAUUUUUAUGCUUAUUUUCUGUCAACACUAAUGAAGUCAACAUUGCCUGAAUGUCUGAAUAAUGAAACACAUCCCUGUUUAAAAGUAUGUAACUGAAAAAGAAAUAAAAAAAAAUAAAAGUAGUUUUUUUAAACUUGCUCUUUCCCAUUUCCUCUAAAGAUGGGUAAAAUAAUGUCACUCCCUAAUUUAAGAUAGGAAUUAUAAAAAUUUGGUUUAUUUAGUCUGUUAUAUAUGAGAAGCAGAGCUAAAGGAAUAUGCUUUUGUUAUUUUAUGUUUUGUUUUGCUUUCUUGAAAUCCAGUGGUAAAAAGCACACACUAGGAAGGAUCUAAGCUUUCUUUAAUAUAAAAAAAAUUAUACUUCUCUGAACUGUUUAAUAGAGCAAUAAUUAAAUACAUCUUCUGAUAAAUUAA